GUCCCGGUGGAAGGGAGUAUCGCGGAAAGGGGACUGCACGACUUUUCCCUGAAGCCCACCUGACAAUCGCUGUAUCAGGCAGCGAGCGUUGCCUGCCACCUUCACACCCUCCCGGUGUGCGCUUGAAGUCGCUUUGAGAUUGAAUGGGGUGGCUCGGGCAAUGACGUGCGUGGUAGGACAUGGGGAAUCCUGAGCCGAGCUGGAGAUGGCCAAAGCCCGGAACCAACUGGAUGCUGUCUUGCAGUGUCUGCUGGAGAAGAGUCACAUGGACAGGGAGCGUCUGGAUGAGGAAGCUGGGAAAACACCCUCAGACACCCACAAUAAGGACUGCUCCAUCGCAGCCACUGGCAAAAGGCCAUCUGCCCGCUUCCCCCACCAGCGGAGGAAGAAGAGGAGGGAGAUGGAUGAUGGGCUGGCUGAGGGAGGGCCGCAGCGAUCCAACACAUAUGUGAUCAAGCUGUUCGACCGGAGCGUGGACUUGGCCCAGUUCAGCGAGAACACGCCACUGUACCCAAUCUGCCGCGCCUGGAUGCGCAACAGCCCCUCUGUGCGCGAGCGUGAAUGCUCUCCCAGCUCACCCCUGCCCCCGCUGCCUGAGGAUGAGGAGGGCUCAGAGGUAACCAACAGCAAGAGUCGUGAUGUGUACAAGCUGCCGCCACCCACACCCCCGGGGCCACCCGGAGAUGCCUGCAGAUCCCGCAUCCCAUCUCCACUGCAGCCUGAGAUGCAGGGCACCCCUGACGAUGAGCCCUCUGAGCCCGAGCCCUCACCCUCCACACUCAUCUAUCGCAACAUGCAGCGCUGGAAACGCAUCCGCCAGAGGUGGAAGGAGGCCUCUCAUCGGAACCAGCUUCGUUACUCAGAAAGCAUGAAGAUCCUACGAGAGAUGUACGAACGACAGUGAUGUUCCCAGGUCCCCCCACACCAGUAAACAUCCCCCAGCUCCACA